ACAACUGUGAAUAGAAGAAAAUGCACCUAUUACUCAUCCGCCUUCUGAGAGAGAAAACAUGUCUUUAACCCAUGCUUGAUACGUAUGCUAAACUUGCAGCCAGUAGCCUUGGGUCAGGAGUUCUGCGUAUUUUCAUAAGAGUUGUUCCUGUUACUCUUCGUGAAUUUUCUCACCAUAAAACUGUUGCCAACGGGGAAGAGGGACAAGAACAUGAAGUGUUUAUGAGGGAGCCUGAAACUGACAACCUGUGUAACUGGAGUGCGUCGUUGGCAUGACACUGGCAGCGCACUGCAAACUUAAGCACCUGUGGACUCCUAAUUAGCUCUUUAAAUUGAACUACAUUAAUUCAGGCAUUCUUGUUUGAAUGCGAACGCCUCCUUUUUCAAGCCACCCCCUGGGCAACCCGAAUCCUUAUAUGACCUCCCUCCUCCUCCUAGUACGGCGCAGGGUUAUAAAAUUAUACACCAUGGCCCUCCUAAAGACACUCUAGGAAAACCAUGUCAUCCUGAUCUUAAAACACCUGCAAGAAAGAGCACAGUACUUCACCAUUAAUAAAGUAGAUAUUUCAUCCUGCUCAGAAAACCAACAUUUCCAGCAAUGGCUUUACUACCGGUGUUGUUUCUGGUUACUGUGCUGCUUCCAUCUUUACCUGCAGAAGGAAAGGAUCCCGCUUUUACUGCUUUGUUAACCACCCAGUUGCAAGUGCAAAGGGAGAUUGUAAAUAAACACAAUGAACUAAGGAAAGCAGUCUCUCCACCUGCCAGUAACAUGCUAAAGAUGGAAUGGAGCAGAGAGGUAACAACGAAUGCCCAAAGGUGGGCAAACAAGUGCACUUUACAACAUAGUGAUCCAGAGGACCGCAAAACCAGUACAAGAUGUGGUGAGAAUCUCUAUAUGUCAAGUGACCCUACUUCCUGGUCUUCUGCAAUCCAAAGCUGGUAUGACGAGAUCCUAGAUUUUGUCUAUGGUGUAGGACCAAAGAGUCCCAAUGCAGUUGUUGGACAUUAUACUCAGCUUGUUUGGUACUCGACUUACCAGGUAGGCUGUGGAAUUGCCUACUGUCCCAAUCAAGAUAGUCUAAAAUACUACUAUGUUUGCCAAUAUUGUCCUGCAAUGAAAACAUAUCUCAAUAAAAGGGAGGGGAUAAACGUUUGGAAAUGUUUUUUAAGGUUGAGACACUUUCAACUUCUCAGAGGAGAACAACUUCUCACUUUCAGUGGUAAUAAUAUGAAUAGAAAGAAUACCCCGUACCAACAAGGAACACCUUGUGCCGGUUGCCCUGAUGACUGUGACAAAGGACUAUGCACCAAUAGUUGCCAGUAUCAAGAUCUCCUAAGUAACUGUGAUUCCUUGAAGAAUACAGCUGGCUGUGAACAUGAGUUACUCAAGGAAAAGUGCAAGGCUACUUGCCUAUGUGAGAACAAAAUUUACUGAUUUACCUAGUGAGCAUUGUGCAAGACUGCAUGGAUAAGGGCUGCAUCAUUUAAUUGCGACAUACCAGUGGAAAUUGUAUGUAUGUUAGUGACAAAUUUGAUUUCAAAGAGCAAUGCAUCUUCUCCCCCAGAUCAUCACAGAAAUCACUUUCAGGCAAUGAUUUACAAAAGUAGCAUAGUAGAUGAUGACAACUGUGAACUCUGACAUAAAUUUAGUGCUUUAUAACGAACUGAAUCAGGUUGAGGAUUUUGAAAACUGUAUAACCAUAGGAUUUAGGUCACUAGGACUUUGGAUCAAAAUGGUGCAUUACGUAUUUCCUGAAACAUGCUAAAGAAGAAGACUGUAACAUCAUUGCCAUUCCUACUACCUGAGUUUUUACUUGCAUAAACAAUAAAUUCAAAGCUUUACAUCUGC